AUUCCCCAGCAAGCUCAGCGUGUAACGUGCGCUAUGGAGCCGAAAGUCGCAGAGCUGAAGCAGAAGAUCGAGGACACGCUAUGUCCUUUUGGCUUCGAGGUUUACCCCUUCCAGGCUGAGGCCUAGACUGGCCCUCUCCAGCCUGGCCUGAACUUUCUGUUUCAGGUGGCAUGGUACAAUGAACUCUUGCCUCCAGCCUUCCACCUACCGCUGCCAGGACCUACCCUGGCCUUCCUGGUACUCAGCACGCCUGCCAUGUUUGACCGGGCCCUCAAGCCCUUCUUGCAGAGCUGCCACCUCCGAAUGCUGACUGACCCAGUGGACCAGUGUGUGGCCUACCAUCUGGGCCGUGUUAGAGAGAGCCUCCCAGAGCUGCAGAUAGAAAUCAUUGCUGACUACGAGGUGCACCCCAACCGACGCCCCAAGAUCCUGGCCCAGACAGCAGCCCAUGUAGCUGGGGCUGCUUACUACUACCAACGACAAGAUGUGGAGGCUGACCCAUGGGGGAACCAGCGCAUAUCAGGUGUGUGCAUACACCCCCGAUUUGGGGGCUGGUUUGCCAUCCGAGGGGUAGUGCUGCUGCCAGGGAUAGAGGUGCCAGAUCUGCCACCCAGAAAACCUCAUGACUGUGUACCUACAAGAGCUGACCGUAUCGCCCUACUCGAAGGCUUCAAUUUCCACUGGCGUGAUUGGACUUACCGGGAUGCUGUGACACCCCAGGAGCGCUACUCAGAAGAGCAGAAGGCCUACUUCUCCACUCCACCUGCCCAACGAUUGGCCCUAUUGGGCUUGGCUCAGCCCUCAGAGAAGCCUAGUUCUCCCUCCCCGGACCUUCCCUUUACCACACCCGCCCCCAAGAAGCCUGGGAAUCCCAGCAGAGCCCGGAGCUGGCUCAGCCCCAGGGUCUCACCACCUGCAUCCCCUGGCCCUUGAUUUUCUCCCAUGUGGACCCUGAUUUAUGGUGGUACUUGCUAGGACUUAAUUGGCUUUGGCAAAGCAAAAGGUUUUGAGUACAAGAUUACUAUUUUUGAUAAUAUAGUAGAGAUCUUCCAUGAAGAUAACAAGGCUCAAGGAAGUUAGGUUUGGCCAAGAUAAAGGCCAGGGAACCAGAAUUCCCAUCUGCCUUCAAAUGAGUUUUUUUUUUUUUUUUAGACAGAGUCUUACUCUGUCACCUAGGCUGGAGUGCAGUGGCACAGUCUCUACUCACUGCAACCUCUGCCUCCUGGGUUCAAGCAAUUAUCUGCCUCAGCCUCCUGAGUAGCUGGGAUGACAGGUGCCUGCCACUACACCUGGCUAAUUUUUUGUAUUUUUAGUAGAGAUGGGGUUUCAUCAUAUUGGCCAGGCUGGUCUUUAACUCCUGACCUCGUGAUCCACCCAUCUUGGCCUCCCAAAGUCCUGGGAUUACAGGAAUGAGCCACCGCACCCAGCCAAGACUCUAUCUGUUCCCAUUUCUAAGCAGUUCCCCAAGAUGUUGUUACAGGGCCUAAGGGGCAAAUAUCCUCUAAAGAGUACCUACCAGCAGGGUGUGGUGGCUCCCGCCUGUAAUCCCAGCACUCUGGGAGGCCGAGGCAGGUGGAUCAUGAGGUCGAGUUUGAGACCAGCCUGGCCAAUACAGUGAAACCCCGUCUCUACUAAAAAUGCAAAGUUAGCCGGGCAUGGUAGCGCAGGCCUGUAGUCCCAGCUACUCAGGAGGCUGAGGCAGUAGAAUCAUUUGAACCAGGGAGGCAGAGAUUGCAGUGAGCCGAGAUUGCAUGGCUGCACUCUAGCCUGGGUGACAGUGUGAGACUCUGUCUCAAAAAAAAAAAAAAAAGUACCUACCUCAGGUAGGGACUGAAUAAACACGUGUAAGGCACUUUGGAAAAAUACCUGGCAUAUAUAGUAAGCAGUAUGUUGGCCAUUACCAAAGGCCCUGGGAAUUCUGUACUGCUGCUCAUGGGUGUAGUCGGUUCUAGAGGGGUGGGCAGGUGGGAGUAGCUGAGGAAGACAAGUGGCUGGAAUGGUAUCACAUGAUACACAGAAGUAUCCUCAGUUCUGAAUCUACCUUGGCCUCAAGGGCCCAGGAGAAUAACUUUUCCCAGCUGACAGCCUCUCUGAGGACAAUGACAUAUGAAUGAGGAUCAAAACGAGCUUUGGCCAGGCACUGUGGCGCUCACCUGUAAUCCCACCAUUUUGGGAGGCUGAGGCGGAGGACCGCCUGAGGCAAGGAAUUCAGAACCACUCUGGGCAACAUAAUGACACUAAAAAAGACUAUCUCUAAUCAAGGCUAGAACCAAGGGAAGGCUAAGAAUUGCCCAGUACUGUGCAACUACGAAAGCCCUACCCAAGGCCACCAGCCUUGUCUUCCUCUUUCCUCUGUCAGUUCAAAAAGAACAGAAACCUCCAGCUCUUUUACAUAGCAGGUACCAGGCAUUUAUCAGAAGAGGCCAAGCUUCUGGUUCCCAUGCAGCCCUUUGAAUAGUGUGUCUAAACAAAAAUAGGUGUCCAAGUAGUCACACUGAGACUUUAACUGGUAACCCAGCCUGUGGCGUCAGUCGCAGUGCUCUGGCCAACACUAUAGCAGGGCUUAUUCUUCUCCCUCAUGUGUAGUGAAACAAAAUGUAACACCUUGGGUUCAUUCAGUUCCAUUCCCUAUAUCUACCUGUGUCAAUAUAAUUCCCUGAUUUGGAGGCAGCUCUCCUCAUUUUCCCCAAAACAGGGAAAGCAAGGAGUAAAUUCCUCUUAAAAUCAAAAGCUAAUAAUAUGCUUCCUAAAAUAAAGACUCAUCAAGGUCUCAGUUCAAGUUUAAUACAAACUACAAAAGAUUAAUGGGUUGCUCUACUAAUACAUCAUACAAACCAGUAGCCUGCCCACAACGCCAACUCAGGCCAUUCCUACCAAAGGAAGAAAGGCUGGUCUCUCCACCCCCUGUAGGAAAGGCCUGCCUUGUAAGACACCACAAUUCGGCUGAAUCUGAAGUCUUGUGUUUUACUAAUGGAAAAAAAAAAUACAGAAGAGGUUUUGUUCUCAUGGCUGCCCACCGCAGCCUGGCACUAAAACAGCCCAGCGCUCACUUCUGCUUGGAGAAAUAUUCUUUGCUCUUUUGGACAUCAGGCUUGAUGGUAUCACUGCCAGGUUUCCAGCCAGCUGGGCACACUGCAAGAGAAAGGCACCACUAAUUAAUAACCUUCUCAAUGGUAUGCACCACCAUUCUCCUAUGGACAAAACCAGUUCUGCACCUGAACACUCAGAUACCAGGAAACCUACCCCUGCAAUCAGUCUUAGAUCAUUCACCCUUUUAGUAUGAGCUAACCAUUUUACAAACAUAUAAUCAUCACCACAGCCUUAAGAUACUAUCAUGCCUAAUUUAUUCAUGUAGCACUUGAAAUUUAAAUUUUCCACAAAAAAAGGCAAAGUUUAAAUAAUUUGCCAACACUCUCUAAUCCUUAAGGGGAAAAAAAAGCUAAAUAAACGACACACAUAGGACUAUGUAAACCCUUAACACUAAACUGUUUCUGACAGCCCUUCAGAGCUCUGAAGACAGCAAACUCAGUCUGCCUUCUCAGCAUUCUUCUAACUCUACCAAACUGGAUAGCCUGAACCUUAUAAAGGAUCAAGAACUUAACAGAAGCCCCCGCUUGUUUCAUUAAGUAACUGCCAUCUACCCCUUGGUAAGCAAAAGGCAGAGUUUGAAAUUUUUCAUAGAUUUAUACAGAAAGCACAGCCUUCAACCUUUUCCUGACAAUGCCUAAGAAUGUGCCUCAGGCUAGCCUGAAGAAAAUGAGGCAAGGGGACUAAUCUCUUAUUUUUCUUUUUUUUUUUUUUUUUUUUUUUUUUUGAGAUGGAGUCUCCCUCUGUUGCCCAGGCUGGAGUACGGUGGCGCAAUCUCCACCUCCGUCUCACUGCAACCUCGGUCUCCCGGGUUCAAGCGAUUCUCCUGCAUCAGCCUCCCAAAUAGCUAGGAUUACAGGCGCCCACCACCACACCUGGCUAAUUUUUGAGACAGUCUCACAUUGUCGCCCAGGCUGGAGUGCAGUGGCGCGAUCUCAGCUCACUGCAAGCUCCACCUCCGGGGUUCAUGCCAUUCUCCUGCCUCAGCCUCCCGAGUAGCUGGGACUAUACAAAAAUAGUGGGGCGUGGUGGUGGACCCCUGUAGUCCUAGCUACUCAGGAGGCUGAGGCAAGAGAAUCACUUGAACCCAGGAGGUGGAGGCUGCAGUGAGCUGAGAUCACACCACUGCACUCCAGUCUGGGCGACAAAACAAGACUCUGUCUCAAAAAAAAAAAGUGUUUGGCAUUCAUUGGCUCUUAAAUGGUACCUAUUUAAGAGGCUGUACAUGUUCCAGUGGGAUGGGAAGCAGCAGAGACCAACAGAGUCUGAAGAAGCAAGCUUCUGAGUUAUGAAAGCCUGGGUUCAGGAGACUAACCUAUAUGUAGGUUCCUAGGAAAGUCCAGUUAAAGGGCCUACUUUGCCACUGCUGCCUCCUUCUUAAUGCUGAACCUCAUCUCCCACAAGGGGGCAGUCUCAGCAGGUGUCAGCUGAGCCAUGUGUCAUCUGUCCAGGCUAACUGCCCACACAUCCUUCUGCAAAGGGUACCUCUUGGUUAUCAGUGCUCACUGAUCCCUAUAUAAUCAGACUCUAAUCCCUGUAAAAAGAUUACUUGGUGCUAGCCAAGCUAGCACCUUUGGGUCUUCCCAAACAUACACCACUAAUCCAGACUCUAAUAACUUCAUUUCCUUUAAAUUACAAGAUCAGAGCUGAAAUAGGCCUUAGAAAGCUAGUCUGGGCUGGGCGCAAUGGCUCAGGGGAGGCGGAGGUUGCAGUGAGCCAAGACUGCGCCACUGCACUCCAGCCUGGGCAACAGAGCAAGACUCCAUCUUGCAAAAAAUAAAUAAAUAAAUAAAAAUAUGAACUAUAUGGAUUAACCUCUUCUCUCAAUAAAGUUAUUUAAAAAAUGGCAUGCUUUAUCUCUAGAGGUGAUUCCCAACCAUUUUGUUUUGCCCUAAUACAUCUGUGAGAUCAUCCUACAUUCAGUAAGUUAGAUCUUUGGGAGUGACUGAUUCUAAAUGAGCAGGACAGAAGAGAGGAGUAUGUAUACUUUGAAUAAAAAGCCUUUAUAUUCUC